GAGUUGGUCCCGGCAAGUCCUUGAGCAGUUUGUUCCUCUGUCUUCCCGCUUCCUGGUGCCCCGACUGCGUCCCCACGAACGCCCCGUCCUUACCGCCGGCUGCUGUGGAGUGCCUCGCUGUCUCCCAGGUCCCCGAGUUCCUGGUUUCAGAGAAGAUGACCGAAGAAGUGGAUUUCCUGGGACAGGACUCUGAUGGGGGUAGUGAGGAAGUGGUCCUAACUCCUGCAGAGCUCAUUGAAAGAUUGGAGCAGGCCUGGAUGAAUGAAAAGUUUGCCCCUGAGCUGCUGGAGAGCAAGCCUGAGAUUGUAGAAUGUGUCAUGGAACAGCUGGAGCACAUGGAAGAAAAUCUCAGGAGAGCCAAAAGGGAGGACCUGAAGGUCAGCAUCCACCAAAUGGAGAUGGAGAGGAUCCGCUACGUCCUCAGCAGCUACUUGCGGUGUCGCCUCAUGAAGAUAGAGAAGUUUUUCCCUCAUGUCCUUGAGAAGGAAAAAACACGUCCUGAGGGGGAGCCUUCCAGCCUCUCGCCGGAAGAGUUGGCCUUUGCCAGAGAGUUCAUGGCGAACACAGAGUCCUAUCUGAAAAAUGUCGCCUUGAAGCACAUGCCCCCUAACUUACAGAAGGUGGACCUCUUUCGGGCAGUUCCCAAACCAGAUCUAGAUUCUUACGUGUUUCUGAGAGUGAGAGAACGACAAGAAAACAUACUGGUAGAACCAGACACAGAUGAGCAGAGGGACUACGUGAUUGACCUGGAGAAGGGCUCACAGCACUUGAUCCGAUACAAAACCAUUGCACCUCUGGUUGCAUCUGGAGCUGUCCAGCUAAUUUAAAACUAGGCAUAAACAGCCAGGCAUGGUGACUCAAGCCUGUAAUCCCAGCACUUUGGGAGGCCGAGGCGGGCGGAUCAUGAGGUCAGGAGUUCGAGACCAACCGACCAACAUGGUGAAACCCCAUCUUUACUAAAAAUACAAAAUAAUUAGCCGGGUGUUGGUGGUGUGCACCUGUAAUCCCAGCUACUCAGGAGGCCGGGGCAGGAGAAUCGCUUGAACCUGGGAGCAGGAGGUUGCAGUGAGCCGAGGUCGUGCCAUUGCACUCCAGCCUGGGUGACAGUGAGACUUUGUCUCAAAAAAAAAAACAAAAAACAAAAAAAAAACAAACUAGGCAUAAACUCAUGAGGUCAGGAGAUCAAGACCAUCCUGGCUACUAAACCCCAUCUCUACUAAACCCAUCUCUACUAAAAAUACAAAAAAUUAGCCAGGCAUGGUGGCGGGCCCAUCUACUCAGGAGGCUGAGGCAGGAGAAUGGUGUGAACCCGGGAGGUGGAGCUUGCAGUGAGCCAAGAUCGUGCCAUUGCACUCUAGCCUGGGCGACAGAGCGAGACUCCAUUUCCAAAAAAAACACACUAGGCGUAAACAAGAAUGAAGACCUGGAACCGUAGAGAAAAUACUAGAAACCCCUCGUAUCACGUUGUGCCUGAGGACAAUAAUAAAGUAGUUUACUAGGCAUCAGACAUUCCUCAGCAGUGCUGUGGGUCACGGGCGUGAAGCGGAGCUCGAGGCAGGAUUGCUUGUGUUGCUGCAUGUCCUGUCUGCUGUUUUAGCCCGUGUCAGUAGAUGGGGCCAUUGUACUGUUUGUUCUGCACACUUGGCGGAGCAGCAGAGGCUCUCAGCACGCCUUUUCCCUUUGUAGUAUUUUCUGAGCUAAGGAAAGUCAGGCAGAAGUAGUUCAUAAGAAGGCAUCACUGCCUGUGAUCGGGGCUGCAUUUAGCCCUGACCUGAUAAUGGUAGGAGAGUUCAUUUAGCCUUUCUGCUGCGAAGAUUGUAAAUAGAUUAAAGAAAACAGCUGUGGCCUUCUCCCGUCAUACAUCAUUAGACUGUGUAAACUAACAUUUUAGAACCUCUAAUAUUGGACUUAAAACCAAUUUCUGUCGUGCUUAAUUGAAAAUCACAACUAAACCAAUAAACCAUUAUUAAAUUUCCAUUCUGCAGCAGAAGGCACCUCUGGACGGCUCCCGGCUUGUAGUUUAAUGAAGUAUGUGCUCCCUGCUGUUAACCCGCAGCCCUCCCCAACUCUCCAGCAGCUUUGCCAAGUCAGCCUCCGGGCCAUCUGGCUGUCCUUGGCCAAGGCACUGUUAACGGAGUGACGUUAACCAUCUUGUAUUGUGACCUGUGGCCGCUUUUCUGGUUUAAGUCCUUCACUUUUUCAAGAGGAAUGGAUGAAAUUAAUGUGCAUGCAGAGUCUCACAGUGAUGCCGGAAGGAAGGAUGUAUAGGCAGUGAAUGAAUGAUCUUUCCUUGAAAUGCUAUAAAAAGCAACCUGCAUUCCAGUCUUUUCUUCCUGGUUGAAGUUGGCAGAUUUCCAUUUGCAGGGUAUGGGCUGCGAGAGUAAUCAGGGUAACAUUGCUGUCAUUUCCAAGAGAAAUCAGUAGGGGAAAGCAAGGGAGGUCUUUUUUUUUUUUCUUUUUUGAGACGGAGUUUCCCUCUUGUUACCCAGGCUGGAGUGGCAGUGGUGUGAACACGGCUCACUGCAGCCUCCACCUCCUGGGUUCAAGAGAUUCUCCUGCCCCAGCCUCCCGAGUAGCUGGUAUUAUAGGUGCACACCACCACACCCAACUAAUUUUUUGUAUUUUUAGUAGAGAUGGGGUUUCAUGAUGUUGGCCAAGCUGGUCUCGAGCUCCUGACCCCAGGUGAUCCACCCACCUCGGCCUCCCAAAGUGCUGGAAUUAUAGGCGUGAGCCACUGCGCACGGCCUGGGGAGGUUUUAUUUCUUGACAAAGGUAUUUGAUACUCGUGCAGUCCCUGGAGGGUCUCACUGGAGAGACAACAUUUAGGCUGAGAUCUGAUUAACAGGAGGCAGCUGCAGUGCAGAGGUCAAAAGGGAGGGUGUUCCAGGCAGAGAAAACAGCCUGUGCAAAGGCCCUGAGGCAGAAACAAACUCUACUUGAGGUCAGCCUGGUUAGAAAGCCCAACUCAAAAUAGAAAGUAUUACAUGAUAAGGUCUGAGGCAGGCUGGACCCAGAUCUUACAGGACCUUGUUAAUAAGGAUCCCAUUUGGUCCCCCACAGUCCUGAGAAGCGGGCAGGGCUGUGGGAAACAGCAGAUAUUUAGUGGUAAGCCUGAGAUCAGAACCCAAGUCUGCACUUCCUAGUCACGUUCUCCCUGUAGUGCUAAGCCCAGAGACCUGAGCUGUUAACCUAGAACAGUGUGCUUCCUAAGCCUUAAUGUGCAUACCCAUCGCCUGGAGCUCGCCUUAAGAUGUAGGUUCUGCCUGAAGCCCAAGUUCAUUUAGUAUGUCAUGGUUAAUUCAGAGUAAAAUCAAGAGUUAGUACUUGAUUUAUGCUUGUUAUAUAAAGAAAGAGACAACUUCACUGUAUGAUCAUUUUGUCACUUUUCAAAAGCAUUUAAUUCCCAUUCAAUUGAAAAUGUUUCAAGAACAAACCUGUUUGGUCAUUUUAUUGAUAUUGCACAUUUGUAUAUGAAUAAAUUUUUGCAAAUUAAAAAAAAAAAAGAUGUAGGUUCUGAAACAGGGUGAGGUCCAGGAUCCUGCCUUUCUAAGGAGCUCCCAUGUUGUGCAGUUGCUGCUGGCCCGGGGACCACAUUGAAUGACGGCUCUACGUCCUCAUGCCUCCAGCUGCUGCCCUGUACAUGUCCAACUGCACGGAGCACUUUACAUCCUCUAAAACCACAGUAAAUUGCUCCAUUUCCUAAAUUACCUCUUCAAGAGAAGACUGGUUUUGAUGUCAUUUUUAAAUAAAGGAGAAGUUGAAUUUCAAAA